ACUCUCCCUGCACAGCUCAGCGGGACCUCAGCCAUGAGACUUCUCAUCCUGGCCCUCCUUGGCAUCUGCUCUCUCACUGCAUACAUUGUGGAAGGUGUAGGGAGUGAAGUCUCACAUAGGAGGACCUGUGUGAGCCUCACUACCCAGCGACUGCCAGUUAGCAGAAUCAAGACCUACACCAUCACGGAAGGCUCCUUGAGAGCAGUAAUUUUUAUUACCAAACGUGGCCUAAAAGUCUGUGCUGAUCCACAAGCCACGUGGGUGAGAGACGUGGUCAGGAGCAUGGACAGGAAAUCCAACACCAGAAAUAACAUGAUCCAGACCAAGCCAACAGGAACCCAGCAAUCGACCAAUACAGCUGUGACCCUGACUGGCUAGUAGUCUCUGGCACCCUGUCCGUCUCCAGCCAGCCAGCUCAUUUCACUUUACACCCUCAUGGACUGAGAUUAUACUCACCUUUUAUGAAAGCACUGCAUGAAUAAAAUUAUUCCUUUGUAUUUUUACUUUUAAAUGUCUUCUGUAUUCACUUAUAUGUUCUAAUUAAUAAAUUAUUUAUUAUUAA